GUAGACUCAUCUUUGUUUUGCUUUAAUUUGCUCUCAGAAUAAAACACAGCAGAAUUGUCCUUUAGGGGGCUUUUACUAUGGAUUGGUUAGUUACUUUAUUGACUGUGUAUUAACACUCUCUGAACUACGUGUUCUGCCUGUUUUUUUACUAAAUUAUACUUUCCAAUCUAGGCAGAUGGUGGUGUCUGCUUUGGAGGCACAUUUUGUUGUCCUUUUUUUUUACACGUGUCUGCUAUUUCCUGGGGUCAUGUCCAUCUCAUAUUUUAGUAGUCAACAAUGAAAGAUUAAAUUACAAAGUACAGGGAAAAGAAUGUAGGAUUUCAUUUCGUUCAUUUAUUAAUCCCUUAGUUAAUUCUAUAAAGCAUUUAUUUGUGUCAGAUACUGUAAUUAAGUGCAAUUUUAAAAAAUCCCAGAUUUUUUAUGCUCUCUCUUAGACCUGCCCAAAUGAUUCCAUCCGUAUCUCCAGAAUUAGUUACUGCAAUAAAUUUGGUUUCCUCCAGACAUUUCCUCAUGUUUUUCUCUAUUGUAUCUUCCACUCUAUUCUCUAAGUCUUUGUCUGGCUUUGCAUGGCUAAAAGCCCAUUCAAAUGAUUUUUCUGAACACAACAGCUUUCUUUUCACAGAGGUGAACUCUGAUCCUUACCUUUCUGGGCACCAAGAAUUAGAGGAGGGUUUGAAAUUAUUUUUCCCCUAUAUCCUGCCAAGAUCUUGCUCAGUGUCCCACUCUCAUCUGGUUCCUACUAGCAAUCAUUUCAUUAAAUGGAAAGCUUUUCUCAAAUAUUGGGGAGCCUAACCCUGAUUGGAUAAGGGAGAAAGAGGCAUGAAAGAACAAGGGAGAGGAAAAGGCAGAGUUUAAAAGGGUCAUUGUCUUUUUGCAGAAGAAACAUCUUCUGCCCCUUAUUCAGGACAGCUAAGAGCACUGGUUCCUCCAGAAUGGGGUCCCCACUUAGUAAUCGUUUAGAAGCAAUCCUGAGGGUGUUGCUGUAGCUUGGUUUAAUCUGUUUCAUAUUAUUUUUUUCAAAGUAGGCAGAUAUAGGAACUGGGUCUCUGGAGGGUAAUCCAUGCCUUCCAAGAGGGCCAUGCAGGUGAUGUUUUUCUAUCAAACCAAGGAGGUUGGUAGCUGCUCACUUCUAGCAGCACAGGAAAUAAAACAUUUGCAGGCUGGAUGUUGCUAUUACUAUUCUAGAUAUCAGAGAAAAAGUUAUAAUCUUCUGAAAAGCAUAAUUUUUUAUCUAUUACAUUUGAAUUCUAUAACUGAGUGCCUUACAUAUUGUCUGAUCUAAUCUCAUUUUACGGAAAGAACUGAAUCCCACAGAUGUUAGCAGUAGCCUGUAUUAUUGAGCACGUCCUUAGCGUCAGACAUACAGAUAUAAUGUACUCUAGAGAUCUUUUAACUCUCGCAACAACCCUAAACUCUAAAAAGUAGGUUCCUUGGGAUUGCCAUAAUAUAUUGAUAGAUAAAGAGGCAAAAGCAUAAGGUUAAGUAACUUGCACAAAGUCGUACAAUCUAGAAAAUGGCAGAGACUUGAACCUAGAUCUUAAUGGCUCCAAAGCCCAUGCUCUUAACCUCAAUGUUAAACUGUAUAAUCUAAUAGGGUUAUUAUAGCUCCCAGUUCUUAUGACCCUACCUUCUAAUUCUCUCUCAAAUCCAUAGUCUGGACUAGUGAUUCUCAAACAUGAGCAUGCACCACAGUCAUCUGGAAGACUUGCCAAACACAGGGUACUGGGUCUGUGGUGGACAGACUCUAAGGUGGCCCCCACGAUCCCUGUCCCUUGGUGUGCACACCUUGGUAUAAUCCCCUUCUCUUGUGCAAGGGAUCUGUGUCUUGUUUCUAAGCAAUAGAAAAUAGCAAAGGUGAUGGGGUGUCACCCUUACGAUUACAAUAGCUUAUAUAAGACUCUGACUUGCUAGCAGAUUUAUUUCAGAGAGUCUUUGCUGGAUGGAUGGAGUAAGUAGCCAUGCUGAGCAAGCUCAUGCAGCAAGGACCUGCAGGGCAGCCUCCAGAUGACAGCCAGCAAGAAGCCAGGGAUCACAGUCCUAUAACCACAAGUGAAUUAAUUCUACCGGCAGCCUGAAUAAGCUUGUAAGUGAUUCUUCCCAUGUUGAACUUCCAGAAGAGAACACAGCCUGUCUGACACUUUGAUUGCAGCCCUAUAGAACCCUGAGGAGAGGACUUAGCUAAGUGGUACCCAGACUCCUGGCCCAUGGGAACUAUGAAAUGAUAAAUAUUUUCUGUUUUAAGCUGCUAAUUUUGUAGCAAUUUGUUACACAGAAAUAAAUAACUAGCACCGCCCCCCCCCCCGCCCCCCAACCAGCCCUGAGUUUCUUACUCAGUAGACCUGGCACAAUAAUUUGUACUUAUAAGAAGAUUCCAGAGGUCAGUGAUGCUACUGGUCCAGGGACCGCACUUUAAGAAUCAGUUCCUAGAUGUAGAGAAUCCCAUUAUAUCCUACUUGUCCUCCCUAUACUUUCAAGUUUCCCUCCUCUGCCUAGAACCAUCCCCCAGGCUCCUUUUGGAUUAACUUCUGAUCUCUCUUUAGAUAAACUCAUACUUACCUUUCAGUUUAAGUGUUAUUUGCUCAGCAAAGCCUUCUCCCACCUCAGCCUGGAUGAGGAGUCUUUGUUACACACUGACUAAAAGCACGGGCACUGAAAUCCACCUGCCUGGGUUUGAAUUUCAGCUCUGCCACUUACUAGCUGUAAAAUCAUGGGCAAAUUUAUUAACCUUUCUAUGUCUCCAUUUCCUCAACACUAAAGUGAUAAGCACAGGUUACUUCAUAAAACUAGGAAAGUUAAUAUCUUCCAUAUUAAAAUUGGGUGAUAGUAGUAGCUUACUCCAUCCACCUAGGAGAGUCAAAUAAGGUAAGUGCAUAGUACUAUGCCUGGUGAGUAAGUUCUCAGUAAAUGGUGUUGGUGGUGGUUGCAUUUUGUGUUGAUGUUACUCUUGUGAUCUCUCAUAGACGCAUUUACUUCACUGCUUAGAAUUCUGCAUUUGUUAAUGUGAAUGCUUAUCUCACUUUCUAGAUGAUAAAUUCCAUGAGAAUGAGAACCAUGCCCACUCUUGCUUCUCAUGUUAGCCCUAGCACUUAGGGCAGUACCUGGCAGAACAGGAAUAGUAAAAAAUUACAAUAUAUAUUUGAUGAAUGAAUGAAUACUCUCAGGGCUAGAGCCACACUCUGGAGGCCUAUUCCCGAUCAUUAUGCAUUUUUUCCAUCUGGUUGGAAUGCACUUUCCUCUGUAUUUAGUCCCCGAAUGUACUUAUCCUUUCGCCCUGCUCUUCACUCAAUUGUGGUGAGAUCUUAUGGAGAGUCUGUUAGGUUGGUCCUUGGUCUGGGAUUGCAGUGGCCUCUAUACGAUAGUUUGUUUUUGCCAUGGAACAUAGAGGAGAGUUGGUCAUGGAUAAUUGUACUUGGGUACAAAUUUUUAAAAAAGUACAAAAAAAAGCAAAACAUCUUUGCUUUUUGAGAUUUUCCUUCUUACUUUAAUAUCUUUCCAAAUUUAUAACACCUACCAGAUGCUAAUAGGACAUCAUUGCUCUAUAUCAAACUAUAUUAGUUCCUCUCUGAGAUGAAGAAGGGUGUAUCCAGAACUCAGCUACUGUUUGUCGGGCUGGACGGAGUAGGGGAAAAUACAUUAUGACACAGCUCUCUGCAGAAGGCUGAAAAGUAGCUCAGUUCCAUUCUUGAUUCCAAAAAGUUAAAUGAGUUUUCGUAGUUUUUUUCUUUUUCUUUUUUUUUUUUUUUACUUUCUCCCAUGAGCAGCGAAAGAGGCAGCUCAGAAAACUAGUCUGCAGGGUUCUCUGGAGAUGUUUUCCCUCCCUACCCCAUUUCAUUAACCUUUCUUCUGAAACUACUUUUGAAUGUCUGGGUUUAAUUAAGAGAUUCUGCAUGCAGUAUGGAAAGAGCCCAUCUCUCCUUUUGGCUUAUUCCUUCAUCUGAUUUGGGUUGAAAAUAUACUUUUUUAAGAAUUAGUUAUAAUUGUUUUUGACAAAAGAAAUAGCUCUUUUUUAUGUCUGCAAAUCCUUAAUGCUGGCUUAUAUGCAGCUAAUGAUGAUAGCCAUCGGCAUAAUCAGUUCUAAUGGUCUCUACUGUCUUUCUAGCUUUGCAUAUAGGAAUGUAAUUCAAAUUUCAGAAAGGCUGGGGCUGAAUGGCUCUUUGUUCUGCAUUUAAAAUAUUACUACAGUGUUCACUGGAAAGAGGUCUGUUAUUACAAACUGGAUUUGAGUCUCAACUUUACUUUGUAGCUCUGGGAACCUGGGUAGAUUCUUGAGUUCUCUUAGGCUGUCUCCUCUCCUUUCAGAUAACUUCCUGAGAAGUGGAGACUAUCAAAAAACAUUGUGUAUGAAAGGAUUUUGUAUGCUGUAAAGUGGUGGGGUUUUUGUUUGUUUGUUUUGUUUGUCUGCUUGUUUUUUGCUGUUGUUGUUGCUUUUACCUAGAAGUGAUUAUUAUUUCUAAUUCAAAUCAUCCUCCCAAAGAUUUUUUUUGAAUUUCUUUGGAUGUUGCAUUGAAGGAAAAAAGCUCAAUUUUUAUCCUGAGUUUUAAAAAAUUAGACAGUAAAACCUUAAAUUGGUUAGCAGUUGCAGUUUAUAAAGCAUUCAUAGAAUUCAUAAAACAUUUUCUCACACAUUAGCCUGUUCCCAGUCUUCUGGAGGAAAGGGGCUGCUGAUCUUGCUAGGCAGCUUGAUGUAUAUAUUUCAUUUAAUCCAGAAACCUUACAAGAUAGCUAAAAUUAGCUUCACUUUUUAGAUAGGAAAACUUAGGAUCAAGGUCCAAGGUCAUAAGGUUUGAACUCCCAUCUUUAUAAUUCAUCAUUUCCUUGACCUCGGUGGCAUAAUUCUCUUCUGUGAAGAGGAUUGUAAAUAAAACAGUUAGGGGCCUUGAGUUUGCCUAGAGGACCAUUAUUGAAAUUCUUCUUUCAAAUCUUAACGUUUCCCUAUGUUAGCAGAGAAAAAUGGGAUUAGGAAGGACCUUUAAUGAUUGAUUCCUCUACUUAGAUGUCAAGAAAGGCCAUUGUAACCACAGCAAAGAUUUAGCACUCAAGUACUCUAGCUUAGUGACUCUCAGCUGGUGCCAAUUCUCCCUUCCUCCUGUCCCUAAGGGACAUUGGCCUAUAUCUGGAGCCAUUUAUUUGCCACAACUGGCCAGGUACUAUGGGUAUCUAAUGGAUAGAGACCAGAGAUGCUGCAAAACCUACUGCAAUACACAGGAGAGCCCUACCUUUCACACAAAGAAUUGUAAGUCCCAACAUAUUAAUAGUGCUCAGCUGAGAAACCUUGUGGGAAGAAUCAGGAAGGCUUCCUGGAGAAUGGGGAUACUACAACUGGGAUUUUGAAGAUAAUUUAAAAUUCUCCAAGCAGACAAUGGAAGGAAAGGCAUUCCAGACAAAGAGUAUGGCAUUUGAAAAAGUAUAGAGGCCUGAAAUAGUGCUGUAUAUGUAGGAAUUUCUGGGCUCUUUGGCAUUGCUGUAGCAUUUCUGGGAGGAGCAGUAGGGGGAUGACAUUAGAGCAAUGUGUUGAGUUUCUUUUCUCCAACAGUAAUUCACAUUAAGAGUAGAAUUGUAAAUUCGUUUUGUUCCUGAGGAUAAUUCUUUCUGCUAGACAACCUGUGACCAUUGUCACCAGUUCUUAAGAGAGUCAUGCAGAGACUACUCUUGAUCGAUGAUACAGGUGGGUAGCCUGGCCAUGGCUCUUGACAGACCUGUGCUUAUUUUCUUUCAGUGGGCACCUAUAAGGAUUGAACCACAGGAAGGUGAUGUACCACCCUGAGCUGAAUACUUCCUCACUAGCUUUUUUGUAUCCACAGCCCCUGUAUCCAUCUGCGUGGUCUAUAUUCCAAAGUAGUUUGAUGGGGCAGCAUGCAGAAGUGUGUUCUUAUGCAGUAAUAUAGUGGUACUCAGUGUGUUCUUAUGCAGUAAUUGCUCUCCAGCCAAAGCAAUUUGCUAGACCUAGGUGAUUCUGAACUAAUUUGUAAUUAUAUAUGUACUCCUAUUACAGAAGAUUGCCCUCCUUUGUGUUUUAACACAGCUUCAAUUUGGUUAAAAUAAUCCUAUUUAAUGAAUGCUAUUCAUCAACUAUAUAUAUAUUUCCAUCCAUCCAUCCAUCCAUCCAUCCAUCCAUCCAUCCAUCCAUCCAUUCAUCCAUCCAUCCAUCCAUGCUCACUAACCUUGGUUUGAGUUUGAGUCCUGGCUUUAGCAUUUGCUUGCUGUGUGACUACUGGCAAAUGCUUUAACCUCUCUAAGAUGCAAUUUCCACAUCUUUAAAAUGGAGAUCAUAAUAAUUAGCAAGGUUGUAUUCUGUACCAGAGAUAAUACGUGAAUAAUCUAAAACAGUGAUGUAUUAGUAGUAGUAGAUUUGCUAAAUAAAUGGUAGCUUUAUUAUUAUUGCUACUAUGACAAUGAUGAUGACAGUGUCCAGAGCACUUUAAUCUAUGGUUUGGAAGAUAGGAAGGUUGAUAAAUCCCUUCCUAUCUUUUGGAGUUCAUACUGGGAGCUUCCCCUCUCCAGCCCAACAUAAUUGAUACCACAUGGUCCCAACAUCUAAAUCUGGUACCAACCCUGUGGCAGCAACAGAAAGCCUGAGCUUUGUGACCUUGGGUAGGUUAUUUAACUUCUCUGAGCAUCACUUGGUAAUUUGCAAGAAUUAAAUGAAAUAAAACAUUUAAAAUUCUUGGCACUCAGUAGAUGCUGAACAAAUGCUGGUUCCCUUCUCCCUGAGGCAGUCAUCAUCAAGAUGUUCUGUGGGUUUCACUGCUGGCAAAAACAAAUGAGGUUAAAUAAAAGUCAGAGGUGAAAAUAAGAGGAGUUAACAGAGUUUCUGUUUUGUUUUUUCUUUACAUUUUCUACAAUUUACAGAGAUUCUUCUCUCCCUCAAACUUAAGUAGAUUUCAAACGACUUGUCAUUCUCAAGGUGAAAUUUAUUUUUAUGCUUUCUUCUCUAAGUCUAGUCAAGACGUUUCUCAUAGAUGGGUUUGACCUUUGAUGGAGAUGUCUCAAACCUGCCUGCACCAUUCUCCAGAAAUGAAUAUUUUUUCCCCAAUCCUAGCUUGAAUUCUCAGAAUUUCUCCUCCAGAUAAGUCACUUCUGCCCUGGCCUCUUGGUUUGUUUGCAUUAGACCCUCAGAUAAUGGGCAGAAGUUUCCUCCCUAUGCCCAGAGCUCUUGCCCUUUGGCUGUUGGCCUUACUCUGAGCUGCAGACACUGGCUCCUUACUGGUGGUGUUCCUGCCUUAAGUACUUAGAGUUCCCCUGGCCUGGACUGAACUCUGCCUAGAACUCAGAUCUCUUAAAUAAGCUUCCUCUCAAUCUUUUGUUAUUUUCACAGACACCUGCACGGCUUGCUGUGCUUUGAAUACACUAACACUUCACUCAUGCUGACUGGAUGGGUCUUCCACACUCAAGGAUGGGCUUGAAUGUUCCUUCUAGGCCUCAACUGGGAGGACUCUGCUUCUUCCCAUGUGUCACAUAGCACUUGUAAUACUUACAGUGUGUGUCCCCAGCAAGAUUUUUGAGUUCCUAGGUGACAGGAGCUAUGAAGAGUCAAUCUGCUCUGAAUCCUUUAGGAUGUGGCCUAGUGCUUAUAAUUAAGGAGACAGAGAAGGAAGCAAAAGGGACUAACAGACGUGCUGAAGGCUAGUGGUAACAAUGCAGCAUGAGUUGAUGGCUCAAACUUCAUUCUAUUAGUACCCCUGGGAAUGAACCACAUGGGAAGUGAAGACACCAGGAGAUACAGGAGUUUCUGAGGCUGAACAGGAAUCAGCAGUGGGCUGCAAGAAUGACCUAGUGGAAUGAGCAGAAGCUACACAGACCUGAGAGAAGUCUUAAUUCUGUCAUUUAACAGCUGUAUGAUCUCAUGCAAAUUGUGGGUCAUCACUGCCGCAGACAUUCUUGAUCGGGAGACAAUGGGGUCAUACUGGCUAACAGUGUAUGCCACAGACAGGGGCGUUGUUCCACUCUACUCCACCAUUGAGGUCUACAUUGAAGUUGAAGAUGUGAAUGACAAUGCCCCGCUGACCUCAGAACCUAUAUAUUAUCCUGUUGUCAUGGAAAACUCUCCAAAGGACGUAUCUGUCAUUCAGAUCCAGGCUGAAGAUCCUGACUCCAGUUCCAAUGAAAAACUGACAUACAGGAUUACAAGUGGAAAUCCUCAGAAUUUUUUUGCCAUCAAUAUCAAAACAGGUCUGAUUACAACAACUUCAAGGAAAUUGGAUCGAGAACAGCAGGCAGAACAUUUUCUGGAGGUGACUGUGACAGAUGGUGGUCCCUCUCCAAAACAGUCAACCAUUUGGGUGGUGGUUCAGGUUCUAGAUGAAAAUGACAACAAGCCCCAGUUCCCAGAGAAGGUCUACCAGAUCAAGCUGCCAGAACGUGACCGAAAGAAGAGAGGAGAACCGAUUUACAGGGCUUUUGCAUUUGAUAGAGAUGAGGGCCCCAACGCAGAAAUCUCCUACAGUAUUGUGGAUGGGAAUGAUGACGGAAAGUUCUUUAUUGACCCUAAAACUGGGAUGGUUUCUUCUAGAAAGCAGUUUACAGCAGGCAGUUAUGACAUCCUAACGAUAAAGGCAGUGGACAAUGGGCGCCCACAGAAAUCCUCCACGGCCCGCCUCCACAUUGAAUGGAUUAAGAAACCACCCCCUUCACCUAUACCAUUGACCUUCGAUGAGCCGUUUUAUAACUUCACAGUCAUGGAAAGUGAUAGAGUGACUGAAAUUGUAGGGGUGGUGUCUGUGCAGCCAGCUAACACCCCUCUGUGGUUUGACAUAGUUGGUGGCAAGCAUGCUCGAGAGAUGUUCUAUAUUCUACAGACAGCUUGUGGGCAGAACUGUUCAACAGAAGGGGGGAAUUUUGACAGCGCUUUUGAUGCAGAGAAGGGUGUUGGGACAAUUGUCAUCGCAAAACCUUUGGAUGCAGAGCAGAGGUCCAUCUAUAAUAUGAGUGUGGAAGUCACCGAUGGGACAAAUGUUGCUGUUACUCAGGUAUUUAUCAAAGUGCUGGAUAAUAAUGAUAAUGGCCCAGAAUUCUCUCAGCCGAAUUACGAUGUGACAAUUUCCGAGGAUGUGCUUCCAGACACGGAGAUCCUGCAGAUUGAAGCCACAGAUAGAGAUGAGAAGCACAAGCUGAGCUACACUGUUCAUAGCAGCAUCGACUCCAUCAGCAUGAGAAAAUUCCGGAUUGACCCUAGCACUGGCGUGCUCUAUACUGCCGAGAGGCUGGACCAUGAGGCCCAGGACAAGCACAUUCUCAACAUAAUGGUCAGAGAUCAGGAGUUUCCUUAUCGAAGAAACUUGGCCCGAGUCAUUGUGAAUGUGGAGGAUGCUAAUGAUCACAGUCCUUAUUUUACCAACCCACUGUAUGAAGCGUCUGUGUUUGAAUCUGCUGCUCUGGGAUCAGCUGUUCUGCAAGUGACGGCUCUGGACAAAGACAAAGGAGAAAAUGCAGAACUCAUAUAUACCAUAGAAGCAGGGAACACUGGGAACAUGUUUAAGAUCGAACCGGUCCUAGGCAUCAUCACCAUUUGCAAAGAACCAGACAUGACGACGAUGGGUCAGUUUGUCCUAUCCAUCAAAGUCACAGAUCAGGGAUCCCCGCCAAUGUCUGCUACUGCAAUUGUGCGCAUUUCCGUCACCAUGUCUGACAAUUCUCACCCCAAGUUCAUUCACAAAGACUACCAAGCAGAAGUAAAUGAAAAUGUUGACAUUGGAACAUCAGUCAUUCUAAUCUCUGCCAUCAGUCAAUCUACCCUCAUUUAUGAAGUCAAAGAUGGAGACAUUAAUGGGAUCUUUACCAUAAAUCCAUAUUCUGGAGUCAUCACCACUCAGAAGGCCCUGGAUUAUGAGCGCACAUCCUCUUAUCAACUCAUCAUUCAGGCCACCAAUAUGGCAGGAAUGGCUUCCAAUGCUACAGUCAAUAUUCAGAUUGUUGAUGAAAAUGAUAAUGCCCCAGUUUUUCUCUUUUCUCAAUACUCAGGCAGCCUAAGUGAGGCUGCCCCAAUUAAUAGCAUUGUCAGGAGCUUGGAUAACAGCCCACUGGUGAUUCGAGCCACAGAUGCUGACAGCAACCGGAAUGCUCUGCUUGUGUAUCAGAUUGUGGAGUCAACAGCAAAAAAGUUUUUCACGGUGGACUCCAGUACAGGUGCAAUCAGAACAAUUGCCAACCUGGACCAUGAAACCAUUGCCCAUUUCCAUUUUCAUGUGCAUGUGAGAGACAGUGGUAGCCCCCAACUGACUGCAGAGAGUCCCGUUGAAGUCAACAUUGAGGUGACAGAUGUGAAUGAUAACCCACCUGUUUUUACUCAGGCUGUGUUUGAGACUAUCUUACUUCUACCUACCUAUGUUGGAGUGGAGGUUCUGAAAGUUAGUGCCACAGAUCCUGACUCUGAGGUACCCCCUGAACUGACAUACAGCCUAAUGGAAGGCAGUUUGGAUCAUUUUUUAAUUGACUCAAACAGUGGAGUACUUACCAUAAAAAACAACAACCUCUCCAAGGAUCACUACAUGCUGAUAGUUAAGGUGUCUGAUGGAAAGUUCUACAGUACCUCCAUGGUCACCAUCAUGGUUAAAGAAGCCAUGGACAGCGGCCUCCACUUUACACAAAGCUUCUAUUCCACCUCAAUCUCAGAGAACAACACUAACAUAACCAAAGUUGCUAUUGUCAAUGCAGUUGGAAAUCGCCUUAAUGAGCCCUUAAAAUACAGCAUCUUAAACCCAGGAAAUAAGUUCAAGAUAAAAUCUACCUCAGGGGUCAUUCAGACGACUGGAGUCCCCUUUGACCGUGAAGAACAAGAGUUAUAUGAGCUGGUGGUAGAAGCCAGCCGUGAGCUGGACCAUCUGCGUGUGGCCAGAGUGGUGGUCAGGGUUAACAUUGAAGACAUAAAUGACAAUUCUCCAGUCUUUGUGGGCCUCCCAUACUAUGCUGCUGUUCAAGUGGAUGCGGAACCCGGGACUCUGAUUUAUCAGGUGACAGCCAUUGACAAAGAUAAAGGUCCAAAUGGAGAAGUGACCUAUGUCCUGCAGGAUGACUAUGGCCACUUUGAAAUUAACCCUAAUUCAGGGAAUGUUAUUUUAAAGGAAGCAUUCAACUCUGACUUGUCCAACAUUGAGUAUGGAGUCACCAUCCUAGCCAAGGAUGGCGGAAAACCUUCUUUGUCUACAUCUGUGGAGCUUCCCAUCACUAUUGUCAACAAAGCAAUGCCUGUGUUUGAUAAGCCCUUUUAUACAGCAUCUGUCAAUGAAGACAUCAGAAUGAACACACCCAUCCUAAGCAUCAAUGCCACCAGUCCAGAAGGCCAAGGCAUCAUAUAUAUCAUUAUCGAUGGGGACCCUUUUAAACAGUUUAACAUUGACUUUGACACUGGGGUCCUGAAAGUUGUUAGCCCUUUGGAUUAUGAAGUUACAUCUGCUUACAAGCUGACAAUAAGAGCCAGCGACGCCCUUACUGGUGCUAGGGCUGAAGUCACUGUUGACUUGCUAGUUAAUGAUGUAAAUGACAACCCCCCUAUUUUCGAUCAGCCUACAUACAAUACAACACUAUCAGAAGCAUCUCUUAUUGGGACACCUGUUUUACAAGUUGUCUCUAUUGAUGCAGACUCAGAAAACAAUAAAAUGGUACAUUAUCAGAUUGUCCAGGAUACCUACAAUAGCACAGAUUAUUUUCACAUAGAUAGCUCAAGUGGCUUAAUCCUGACAGCACGAAUGCUGGACCAUGAGUUAGUACAACACUGCACUUUGAAAGUCAGAUCAAUAGAUAGUGGCUUCCCAUCACUGAGCAGUGAGGUUCUCGUUCAUAUCUACAUCUCUGAUGUAAAUGACAACCCUCCAGUUUUUAAUCAGCUCAUUUAUGAGUCAUAUGUGAGUGAAUUAGCCCCCCGGGGCCAUUUUGUAACCUGUGUACAAGCCUCUGAUGCAGACAGCUCUGAUUUUGACCGGUUGGAAUAUAGCAUUUUAUCUGGGAAUGACCGGACGAGCUUUCUGAUGGACAGCAAGAGUGGAGUUAUCACAUUGUCCAACCAUCGGAAGCAGCGGAUGGAGCCUCUGUACAGUCUCAAUGUGUCUGUCUCUGAUGGGUUGUUCACCAGCACUGCACAGGUGCAUAUUAGGGUACUUGGGGCUAACUUGUACAGCCCUGCCUUUUCACAAAGCACAUACGUAGCUGAGGUGAGAGAGAACGUGGCUGCAGGAACAAAGGUAAUUCAUGUUCGAGCCACAGAUGGUGAUCCAGGGACUUAUGGGCAGAUCAGCUAUGCCAUCAUCAAUGACUUUGCCAAGGAUCGAUUCCUCAUAGACAGCAAUGGGCAGGUCAUCACCACAGAAAGGCUAGACCGGGAAAACCCUCUAGAAGGGGAUGUUAGUAUUUUUGUGAGGGCCCUUGAUGGUGGAGGGAGAACAACUUUCUGCACUGUGAGAGUGAUUGUUGUGGAUGAAAAUGACAAUGCUCCCCAGUUCAUGACAGUGGAAUAUAGAGCCAGUGUCAGGGCAGAUGUUGGAAGGGGCCACUUGGUCACUCAAGUUCAAGCCAUAGAUCCCGAUGAUGGAGCAAAUUCAAGGAUUACUUAUUCCCUCUAUAGCGAGGCCUCUGUUUCAGUGGCCGACCUCCUGGAAAUCGAUCCUGACAAUGGCUGGAUGGUCACAAAGGGUAAUUUUAACCAGCUGAAAAAUACAGUGCUUUCGUUCUUUGUCAAAGCAGUAGAUGGGGGCAUCCCAGUAAAGCACUCCCUCAUUCCUGUCUAUAUCCACGUCUUGCCCCCUGAAACGUUCUUGCCAUCAUUCACCCAGUCUCAGUAUUCCUUUACCAUUGCAGAAGAUACAGCCAUUGGGAGUACAGUGGACACCCUGAGGAUUUUGCCCAGUCAGAAUGUCUGGUUCAGCACAGUUAAUGGGGAACGGCCAGAAAAUAACAAAGGGGGCAUAUUCGUCAUAGAACAGGAAACAGGCACUAUUAAGCUUGACAAACGCCUUGACCGUGAAACCAGCCCAGCUUUCCACUUUAAAGUAGCAGCCACUAUACCCCUGGACAAAGUAGACAUUGUGUUUACUGUGGAUGUAGAUAUCAAGGUAUUGGAUUUGAAUGACAACAAGCCAGUCUUUGAAACUUCAAGCUAUGACACCAUUAUAAUGGAAGGGAUGCCUGUUGGCACCAAACUCACACAAGUGAGAGCUAUUGAUAUGGACUGGGGAGCCAAUGGACAAGUCACUUACUCCCUCCACUCGGAUUCCCAGCCCGAAAAGGUAAUGGAAGCAUUCAAUAUUGACAGCAACACGGGCUGGAUCAGUACCUUGAAGGACCUAGAUCACGAGACAGACCCCACAUUCACCUUCUCUGUGGUGGCCUCUGACCUUGGAGAGGCAUUCUCUCUUUCCUCCACGGCCUUGGUCUCUGUCAGAGUGACAGAUAUAAAUGACAAUGCACCAGUCUUCGCGCAGGAAGUGUACCGAGGGAAUGUGAAGGAGAGCGACCCACCGGGCGAGGUGGUAGCCGUCCUCAGCACCUGGGACAGAGACACAUCCGACGUUAAUCGCCAAGUGAGCUACCAUAUUACAGGAGGAAACCCUCGAGGAAGGUUUGCUCUGGGCCUGGUGCAAAGUGAGUGGAAGGUCUAUGUGAAGAGGCCUCUAGACAGAGAAGAACAGGACAUUUACUUUCUCAAUAUCACUGCCACUGAUGGGCUUUUUGUCACACAGGCCAUGGUGGAAGUGAGCGUCAGUGAUGUGAAUGACAAUAGCCCAGUGUGUGAUCAGGUUGCAUAUACAGCAUUACUUCCUGAAGACAUUCCAUCAAAUAAAAUCAUCCUGAAAGUCAGUGCAAAGGAUGCUGAUAUUGGAUCCAAUGGAUAUAUACGAUACUCACUCUAUGGAUCUGGAAACAGUGAAUUUUUUCUAGAUCCAGAAAGUGGCGAGUUAAAAACCUUGGCUCUGUUGGACCGGGAGAGGAUCCCCGUGUACAGCCUGAUGGCCAAGGCCACUGACGGGGGUGGCAGGUUCUGCCAGUCCAACAUCCACCUAAUCCUGGAGGAUGUGAAUGAUAACCCCCCUGUGUUUUCUUCUGACCACUACAACACCUGUGUCUAUGAGAACACAGCCACCAAGGCUCUGUUGACCAGAGUUCAAGCCGUGGACCCCGACAUUGGCAUCAAUAGGAAGGUCGUGUACUCCCUGGCAGACUCAGCUGGUGGGGUCUUCUCCAUUGACAGCUCAUCUGGCAUCAUCAUCCUGGAGCAGCCACUGGACCGUGAGCAGCAGUCUUCGUACAACAUCAGCGUGCGGGCCACUGACCAGAGUCCUGGACAGUCCCUGUCCUCUCUCACUACUGUCACCAUCACCGUUCUGGACAUUAAUGACAACCCCCCUGUGUUUGAGAGGAGGGACUACCUGGUGACGGUGCCUGAGGACACCUCCCCUGGCACCCAAGUCCUUGCUGUUUUUGCCACCAGCAAAGAUAUUGGCACAAAUGCUGAGAUCACUUAUCUCAUCCGGUCUGGGAACGAACAAGGGAAAUUUAAGAUCAACCCCAAGACAGGGGGUAUUUCUGUCUCUGAAGUCCUGGACUAUGAAUUAUGCAAAAGGUUUUACCUGGUAGUGGAAGCCAAAGAUGGGGGCACCCCAGCUCUCAGCGCUGUGGCCACUGUCAACAUCAACCUCACAGAUGUUAAUGACAACCCUCCCAAGUUCAGCCAAGACGUCUACAGUGCGGUUAUCAGUGAAGACGCCUUGGUGGGAGACUCUGUCAUUUUGCUAAUAGCAGAAGAUGUAGACAGCCAGCCCAACGGACAGAUUCAUUUUUCCAUUGUGAAUGGAGAUCGGGACAAUGAAUUUACUGUAGAUCCUGUCUUGGGACUUGUGAAAGUUAAGAAGAAAUUGGACCGGGAACGGGUGUCUGGAUACUCUCUGCUUGUCCAGGCCGUAGACAGUGGCAUUCCUGCAAUGUCAUCAACUGCAACUGUCAACAUUGAUAUUUCUGAUGUGAAUGACAACAGCCCGGUGUUUACACCUGCCAACUAUACUGCUGUGAUUCAGGAAAAUAAGCCAGUGGGCACCAGCAUCUUGCAGCUGGUGGUGACAGACAGAGACUCCUUUCACAAUGGGCCUCCCUUUUCAUUCUCUAUUUUGUCGGGAAAUGAAGAGGAGGAGUUUGUGUUGGACCCUCAUGGGAUCUUGCGGUCGGCUGUGGUCUUCCAGCACACAGAGUCUCUGGAAUACGUGUUGUGUGUCCAGGCAAAGGAUUCAGGCAAACCCCAGCAAGUUUCUCACACUUACAUCCGCGUGCGAGUCAUUGAGGAAAGCACCCACAAGCCCACAGCCAUUCCCCUGGAAAUUUUCAUUGUCACCAUGGAGGAUGACUUUCCUGGUGGGGUCAUUGGGAAGAUUCAUGCCACAGAUCAAGACAUGUAUGAUGUGCUCACAUUUGCCCUGAAAUCGGAGCAGAAAAGCUUAUUUAAAGUGAACAGUCACGAUGGGAAAAUCAUCGCCCUGGGAGGCCUGGACAGCGGCAAGUAUGUCCUGAAUGUGUCUGUGAGUGAUGGUCGCUUCCAGGUACCCAUUGAUGUGGUCGUGCAUGUGGAGCAGUUGGUGCAUGAGAUGCUGCAGAACACUGUCACCAUCCGCUUUGAAAAUGUGUCCCCUGAGGACUUCGUGGGGCUGCACAUGCAUGGGUUCCGGCGCACCCUGCGGAAUGCAGUCCUCACCCAGAAGCAGGACAGCCUGCGCAUCAUCAGCAUCCAGCCCGUGGCAGGCACCAACCAACUGGACAUGCUGUUUGCGGUGGAGAUGCACAGCAGCGAGUUCUACAAGCCAGCCUACCUGAUCCAGAAGCUGUCCAAUGCUAGAAGACACCUGGAGAAUAUCAUGCGCAUCUCAGCCAUCUUGGAGAAGAACUGCUCAGGGCUGGACUGUCAGGAACAGCAUUGUGAGCAAGGCUUGUCACUCGAUUCCCACGCGCUCAUGACCUACAGCACGGCUCGCAUCAGCUUUGUGUGUCCGCGUUUCUACAGGAACGUGCGUUGCACCUGCAAUGGAGGACUGUGUCCGGGGUCCAACGAUCCUUGUGUGGAGAAGCCGUGUCCAGGGGACAUGCAGUGUGUCAGUUAUGAAGCCAGCAGGAGACCGUUCCUCUGCCAGUGUCCACCAGGGAAGCUCGGAGAGUGCUCAGGGCACACUUCUCUCAGCUUUGCUGGAAACAGUUACAUCAAAUAUCGGCUUUCUGAAAAUAGCAAAGAAGAGGAUUUCAAACUAGCUCUGCGUCUUCGAACACUGCAAAGCAAUGGGAUUAUAAUGUACACCAGAGCAAAUCCCUGCAUAAUUCUGAAGAUUGUGGAUGGCAAGCUGUGGUUCCAGCUGGACUGCGGCAGCGGCCCUGGAAUCUUGGGCAUCUCGGGCCGUGCUGUCAACGACGGGAGCUGGCACUCGGUCUUCCUGGAGCUCAACCGCAAUUUCACGAGCCUGUCCCUGGAUGACAGCUACGUGGAGCGGCGCCGGGCGCCCCUCUACUUCCAGACGCUGAGCACUGAGAGUAGCAUCUACUUCGGCGCCCUGGUGCAAGCGGAUAACAUCCGCAGCCUGACUGACACGCGGGUCACGCAGGUGCUCAGCGGCUUCCAGGGCUGCCUGGACUCGGUGAUACUGAAUAACAAUGAGCUGCCGCUGCAGAACAAGCGCAGCAGCUUCGCGGAGGUGGUGGGCCUGACGGAGCUGAAGCUGGGCUGCGUGCUCUAUCCCGACGCCUGCAAGCGCAGCCCGUGCCAGCACGGGGGCAGCUGCACUGGCCUGCCAUCGGGGGGCUAUCAGUGUACCUGUCUCUCACAGUUUACGGGGAGAAACUGUGAAUCUGAGAUUACAGCCUGCUUCCCAAACCCCUGCCGGAAUGGAGGAUCCUGCGAUCCAAUAGGAAACACUUUCAUCUGCAAUUGUAAAGCUGGGCUCACUGGAGUCACGUGUGAGGAGGACAUCAAUGAGUGCGAACGAGAGGAGUGUGAGAACGGAGGCUCCUGCGUGAACGUGUUCGGCUCCUUCCUCUGCAACUGCACGCCGGGCUACGUGGGCCAGUACUGCGGGCUGCGCCCCGUGGUGGUACCCAAUAUCCAGGCUGGCCACUCCUACGUGGGGAAGGAGGAGCUCAUCGGCAUCGCCGUGGUCCUCUUCGUCAUCUUCAUCCUGGUGGUUCUCUUCAUAGUCUUCCGCAAGAAGGUCUUCCGCAAGAACUACUCCCGCAACAACAUCACGCUAGUGCAGGACCCGGCCACCGCCGCCCUGCUUAACAAGAGCAAUGGCAUCCCGUUCCGGAACCUGCGCGGCAGUGGGGACGGCCGCAACGUCUACCAGGAGGUGGGGCCCCCGCAGGUCCCCGUGCGCCCCAUGGCCUACACACCCUGCUUCCAGAGUGACUCCAGGAGCAACCUGGAUAAGAUCGUGGACGGGCUGGGAGGCGAGCACCAGGAAAUGACCACGUUUCACCCUGAGUCGCCCCGCAUCCUGACAGCCCGGCGGGGCGUGGUCGUGUGCAGUGUGGCCCCCAACCUCCCCGCCGUGUCACCCUGCCGCUCCGACUGCGACUCCAUCCGGAAGAAUGGCUGGGACGCGGGAACUGAGAACAAAGGGGUUGAUGACCCGGGAGAAGUGACCUGCUUUGCAGGUAGUAAUAAAGGCAGCAACUCUGAAGUUCAGUCCCUCAGCUCCUUCCAGUCAGAUUCUGGUGACGACAAUGCCUCCAUAGUGACUGUCAUUCAGCUUGUCAACAAUGUAGUUGACACUAUAGAGAAUGAAGUGUCUGUCAUGGACCAAGGACAGAACUACAACCGAGCCUAUCACUGGGACACCUCUGAUUGGAUGCCAGGGGCCCGCCUGUCGGACAUAGAGGAAGUGCCCAACUAUGAGAACCAGGAUGGAGGGUCUGCACACCAGGGGAGCACACGGGAGCUGGAGAGCGAUUACUACCUGGGUGGUUAUGACAUUGACAGUGAAUACCCACCCCCUCAUGAAGAGGAGUUCUUGAGUCAGGACCAGCUGCCUCCUCCUCUCCCGGAGGACUUCCCAGACCAAUAUGAGGCCCUGCCACCCUCCCAGCCUGUCUCCCUGGCCAGCACACUGAGCCCAGACUGCAGGAGAAGGCCCCAGUUUCAUCCUAGCCAGUAUCUCCCUCCUCACCCAUUCCCCAACGAAACGGAUUUGGUGGGCCCGCCUGCCAGCUGUGAAUUUAGUACUUUUGCUGUGAGCAUGAACCAGGGCACAGAGCCCACAGGCCCAGCAGACAGCGUGUCUCUGUCCUUGCACAAUUCCAGAGGCACCUCAUCCUCGGAUGUGUCUGCCAACUGCGGCUUUGACGAUUCCGAAGUAGCCAUGAGUGACUACGAGAGCGUGGGAGAGCUCAGCCUCGCCAGCCUUCACAUUCCCUUUGUGGAGACUCAGCAUCAGACUCAAGUGUAGACAUCACAUCUUGGGUACUUCACCCUGUUUGUUACAGAAAAGUGGAAGCAGAUUGGCUGGGCUUCUGUCCCAGUGGAGCAUUGUCUGUGGAAUGAGAAGGGAAUACUGUAUUUUUCCACUAGAAACUUCUUCACAAGUCAUACUGUCCCAACAAGCAAGCUUGAUUCCAGUUGGGUGAAAAUGAAAGGCUCAGAAAUUGUUUUUGAGAGGUGACUGGUAAUCCUUGAUGUAGGUACCUAUGUUCACAGCUAAAAAUGCAAAGAGGGAAAAAUUAUUUCACCCACUAAGUUAUACAGCCAGUCUUGUAUGGCUUUGUGCAGUAUUGUGCCCUGGAAAGUGUUACAGCAUCAGUCCUUGCAGUAUUAAAAACUGGCAACAAUCAAAGAGGCAUUGUUGCAUGUAAUUUUGAGCCAAUGAAAUGAAAAUAGUAGUAAUGAUUGUUGGAAAAGUUAGUCUCUUAGGCGAAAGAGAAGAGAAACAAAUAUUAUUAAACAAACCAGAAAAUGGGCUGAAGCCUUUUAAAUCAACUCUAUUUUUUUGAUAAGCUGCCCAAUUUUCAGCUAUAAAAUUAGGCUUGAAUAACAUGUUUAGUAUGCUCAGUUAUUUCUGUUUGUUUGUGUUAAGCAUCCAAUCUAAUAUAGUUGGGUUUUAUGAUCUUCAAGAAAGGUAUCAAUGAAGAGCAACAUGAGGCUUUUUGGGUUCCAUUUGGUGGGUGGGGGAGGAAGUUAAAGUUGUUUGAACAUUAGAAAGAAUGUGAUUAUCUGGUUGGUUUUGUGUUUUCUGGUAAAUAUUCCAGUUGGUAAAUCUAACAUUGCUACAGAAGUUGGCUUUGUUCAUAUAGCUUCUCUACAAUUAGAUAUUUUUAGAAGUUUAAGCAAAACUCACAAAUUCAGGGGGGAAAAAAGAAAAAACGAUACCUUCAAAGUUUGCGGCCUAGAUAAUCACAAUUCUUCAUAAUGCAGAGGAAAGGUGUCUGUUAUUCUAAAUCGGUAGCAUCACCAUUAUAAAUACAAUUAUGUUAAGAAAAGAGGAAAGUAGACUAGUUAUUGUGUAUAAAUUAUAAUAGUGUGUGUGUGUCUGGGCCUAUGUACAAAUAUGUGCUUGCACUCAGUAAGGCUGCUCUUGAGGAAAGCUAAUGUGAAGGUUUUGGGAAAUGGACCAUGUUGAAAAUUCUGCCGGCGAGCAUGGCAUACCUUUCAAUUUCUCUGAUCUCUAUGGUGUUAGAGAAACAUCAAAUGCCAUAUUUUACUCUGGUUCAGUUAACUUUAUUUUGGUACUGCCAAUAAAGCAAAAUUGUGCUUUUUUUUUUUUUUCUCAAGACAGAGUCUUGCUCUGUCACCCAGGCUAGAGUGCAAUGGCAUGAUCUCAGCUCACUGCAAUCUCCACCUCCUGGGUUCAAGCGAUUCUCCUGCCUCAGCCUCCCAGGUUGCUGGGGUUACAGGUGUGUGCCACCACGCCUGGCUAAUUUUUUGUAUUUUUAGUAGAGAUGGGGUUUCACCAUGUUGGCCAGGCUGGUCUCAAACUCCUGACCUCGUAAUCCACCUGCCGUGGCCUCCCAAAGUGCUGGGAUUACAGGCAUGAGCCACCGUGCCCAGCCCAAAACUGUGCUUUUUAAAAACAGUAUUUUGUUAUAAUUUUCCAGAACUUACCUCUGUUUUAAAAGUGUGUAAUGUUUGAUUACACCCUGGGAUUCCCUUCUCAUCUGUGGGCUUUGGCCAUGAUUUCCAAAAUUAACAGGAGAAUCAUUCCACUGGAAAUAUAACAAUCCAGUCCUCAAAACUGAAAGUUGACAGGUUGAGGGACUUUCCUUUUUUGCUUCAAUCAGAUUACGGCCGCCUGUGCAGUGGCCAUGGUAAAUAUAUGCAUAUUUGCACUAUCUGCUUAAUGAGCAAAUCUGUGUCCACAGUUUCUGAUGACAUAUGGCAUUGGUGUGUAAAUUGUACUGUCCCUAGUCUGUGCAUUAUUCACUCAGACAUAUUUUUAGUUAUUUCAAUUGCGUUUAAUCCACUUCUUUUUUAUGAGUCAGUGUUUCUGAAUGUUUAUGCAAAAAAAAAAAUCCUUUUUCAUUCCCAAACUUUCUAAGUAAGUGGAUACACUACACUUCACAAGUUUUCCAGCCUUUCUCUUCCUGUCUCUUGGUCAGACCUACUCAUGGAGGUAUUAUCCACACUGUGAUCUUGAAAUAAAUGAAUUUCACUAAGGCUGCUUUCGAGAACAAAGUCUUUGGUAUUUUUCUUAUGUAAGAAGCACAUUUGCAAGAAUCAUGGAAAAAAAUGACAAACUAAUGGCCUAGAAUAGAGUGACUGCUACACUUUAAGUAAUGCAAUGACAUAAAAACCAUCAAAGUAAAACCAACAUGUCAUUUCCUGCCCCCAGGAAAUAUUAGAAUGAGAUUAAUGCUGAUGAGUCCCUACUGCUUACACAGCAUCUCUUUGAGGGAGAAUGCCUGACUGACACAGUAAUGAAAGAAUAAAUAGAUCCUAAUGCAGUCAUGAAGCCACUGAAGAAAAUUGUGCCCACCCUUUGCUGUGACCUAUAUAAAAUAUCUCUUUCUUUGGGAUAUCAUCCCCUGAUUUUCUGCAGAAUAGCUCUGCAGCUAAAUAUAUACCAGGCAAGCAUGUAUUGUGUUUUGAUUUAUUAUCUUUAAACACAUGAUAUCUCUUCACUUUUUGGAAAGUUAGAUUUCUCUGUAGAUUAUGAAAUGCUUUGCAGUCAGGCCAAGAUGCUACUAGGUGGGGAUGAUCACUAAUUCAAAAAAGCUGGAAGAAUCCUAUUUGCUAGUCCAAACUCCUUAUUUUAUCAAAGAGGAAACAUACCCAGAGUGGGAAAGAGACUUGCCCAAGCCCACAGAGGAAGUUAAUUCGCUUAACAAGGAGUAGAACCCAUCCAUCUAGCCAAUAUUCUUUUUACAUCAUAUUGUUCACCCCUACACUGCCUUGAGCAUGGGAGUCACCUGGUUCUGAUGGACCCUCUGACUUCCACCAUUCCUUCUUUGGAAUAUGCUAUAAAAGAAAAUUCAUGGAGAAUAUUUUUCUGAAAGCCUCAUGAUCUUAUGUUUCCUUGCAGUCCCCCUAGGGAGAGGGGUUAUAGAAUUCAUACAUUUCUGUAGACAUUCAUCGAAAUGCUGCUUUUGCCAAAUGAAUGUUUGUAUAAUAGGGAUGAAAUGAUAAUUACAGAGUUCAGCUCAGACCAGUCAUCAGUUGUAGUGAAACUUUGAUUAUACUGUUACCUACUGGUUGCAUUUUUGGUUUUGGUUUUGCAUUUUUUUCUUCCCACAAACACUGGCUACUCUUUGUCCUACCCCCUCCACCAUGAUGAACCAUGUGGAAACUAUUUAAAUCAAUUAAUGUCUUUCUCAUUUUUCGAACAUGUAUGUGCCACCUCCUGGAAGCCAUUUCCCAUAAUCUGUUGUAGGCACUUUACUAGUAUUGCACACAUUCUGGUUAGGUUGAGAAUAGCUAGACUCUUGGUGCUCGUCAUAUAGUAAGCAAGAACUUGGGAGUAAUAAAAGGUGAAUAAAAUGCAUGCUUCAUUUAUUCCCUUUCCUCUAUGAAUAUUUUGCUGCUGCAUUCUAGUCUAUGCCAGCUUUCCAUGUACCCUUGGCCUGCCUAUUCAUGAAAUGCCAUAUAAAAGACUUAGGAACAUGAGUAGGUGGUCCAUGCUUUGAGGUUCAUCCAAUUAGGGAAUAAAUGUGAAAGGCUGGAAAGGGAACUAGUUUCUGGGAUUUGCCUGGAACUUCCCUUGGACAUUACUAGCACAUUCUGGAAAAAAAGCAAGUUGAACAUAUCUACCAUCAGUCCUCUCCUACUUACUUCCCACCCCACCCUAUCCACUACCCCCACUGAUGCUAUGUUUGCAUCAUCAAAGUCAGGGGAAUUGAGAAAAGAGAUUAUCAAAAUAAAUUAUUAAAAUCCAGAAAACAGUUUUAUGUGAAGUAAUUCAGGAAGAUCUAGUGUUCAUUUUGCAUGGAUUGUCCAGAUAAUUGGCUCUUCACUCCGCUGCCUUCCCAGUGCACAGGUAUUGCUAAAGUGGUUAGGCUUUAAUGUUUUAUGUUUUUAGUUUCAAACUAUGGGAAAUGGAGAUUUGAAGAGGCAUUUAUUCCUUGUCAUCAUUUUGUGUGCUCUGUGAGAAGGUGGUUAUAUGUUUUUGCUGGUUUGUGUCCCACAGUGUUCAACUGCACAUUAUUCUGAUGAAAAUCCACAAUGUCUUUGAGCUUCUGGUUGUGUAAUGCUGGGGUUUAAAGUCACCAUUUGUGGGUUUGGCAUCAAUUAAUAUUUAGCCAGCUGGCUAAGAGAUAGGAAAAGAAUAUGAUAUUUCUUUCCUUAUGUAAUAAUGAAAAGCAAUAAUUACAAGUAGGUAAUAAUACACAAAGGCCAUAAUUAGUCUCUUCUAGUGUUUAGAAUGCACUUGAGAAUCGUAGAGUCAUUUGGAGCGUGUUUGGACCAAUUAGUAUGUACUGUAGUACCCUUCUGGCAAACAAAUAACUGAAUUGCUACUAUUUAACAAUCUUAUGAGCCCACACUACUGCAUUUUGGGAGUGGCAAAUGUGUUUGGAAAUGGAAGCAGUUCUUUUUAAGCACUGUAUCAGAGAGAUUGUCUUGUACGUUUGCCUGUUGCAAACAGGCUGGUUUGUAAAAGAUGUAUGUUUUGGUGUUUGAAAUGUUUAUAAAAUUGUAUAUAAAUGGUUUCAAUUUUCCAGGCUUUUGUAGAUACUAUAUUUGAUGCCUAUCAGGAUGCUUUAAUUUGGGGGGUCGAAUAUAAUUGUAAGUCAUCCACGCUGUUGGUCUGCAAACUUUUGAGGUAACUACACACACACACACACACACAAGGAUUUUAGAUUUGAAAAUGAUGUUUUUUACUCAUUUCAAAAUGUACUGUAACCUUUCUUUGGUUCUUACUGUUUUCAUUUAACUUUCUCUGUUUUCAAGAAAAAUUGUCUUUAUUGACAUUUGUAAAAAAGAAUGUGUUUUGCCCAGUUAUUAAGUAUUUUAUUUUUAUGCAAUUUCAGAAUCACAAUGAGGUAUGCCAUUUCUUCAUAUACAUGCACAUUCACCUCAACUUGCACACACAUCACACACCAAACCUUAUGCAAAGGGGAAAGCUAACACUUAGAGUGGAUUUUGUCCCUUAAGGAAAUGGAUUGUUCCUGCAUAUAUUGCUGGUGGCAGUAUUCAGUCUUGUGUUCUUUUUCUAAAAAAAAAGAAAAGAAAAGAAAAAAAAAACAAAAGCAAACAAAAAAAAAGACAGCCAAAAAAAAGAAACAACAACAACAAAAAAAAACACAACAGUGUACAGGUUUGUAACUGCCAAAAUUUGAUGGUUAAAACAAGUUUUCAAGUAAAAAGAAAAAAAUGAAACUA